AGUCGCUAGGAAACGAGCGAGCCCGACGCCAGGGGCGGAGCUCUGGCCUCCUCGCCGAGUUGGGGGAGGCAGGUGCGACAGGAGAAUGGACAGUAAGAAGGGGAGACCCAAAGCUGCAGCUGGGAAGUGGCAGACGCUCCACCCUGGGCCCAAGACAAGAGCUGCUGCUGGGAAGCCCGGGGAGAACCGCCCGCCGCAGAGGAAAGCGGGCUGGCAGGCGAGGGAGCCCGCGUCGGCUGAGAGCCCACAGGCCCCCACAGGGACACCUGGUCGCCAUCACAUGGACACGCUAUUUUUGCACUCGAGGCUAUUCCAGGAAGUCCAUCCAGACAGAGCACGCCUUCCCCAGCCUCCUCUUAUUGGCCUGCAGCCCUGCUCUCCCCACGUCUGGUGAUCUGUAAAGAGGGCUUGUUCUGCGUGGGUGGGACCUGCUCUAGAUCCAUCUUGGAAAAUGAGCUCAUGCCGUUGGUGUAACCACCAUUCCUGCCCCCAUGCCACUCUGCCCCGGGGCCUGCUGGCUGACGUCCAUGGUGCAGUCGUGAUGUCCACGAGCCUGUCUGUGCCCUCGCUGCGGCCGACUCUCUCUAGGAGCGUCCCCACAGGAUGCAGAACCUCCCUUUGAGCUCGGUGUUCCCUGCUCCUCACAGAGCCACCCCCAAGCCUUUCCCAGCUGUCCGCAUCACCACUGUCCCGGGCUCGUUCACUUCAGGCCCUGGAGAGCCAGCCCAGCCCUCACUGGUGUCCGGAGUCAGUGAUACACAGCGCUCAAGUGACUCUUCCCACCCACAGGAAGUGGGUGAUGAGGUGCCCCCCGGGGGCUUCCCUUGCUGCUGCCCGCCAGGAUCUCCCUGCUUGGGACUACAGCAUGCGGGGGAGGUCAGGCUGGAGUUGGUGUGGGAGCCUUUCCCAGCCUUUCCUCUGCAUUGGUGCCCUCCCCAGGAGGCAUCUGAGCUGCAAAAGGGGCGAAUGCGAUGUAGACACUUGGGCCCCGGGACUCGCCUGUGUCAUCUGGGCUGGGCCCCACAAACACCACAAACACCUUUUCCACCACGCAAUAGAUGGCUGCUGGGCUGCCCAGGGGUGUGAUGUGGAGCUGGGAAACCCAGCCUGGGAAGGCAGCAUUCCAGGAGCUGCUUUCCAAAAGAAGAAUAGCCUCCACCAGGAAGGUGUGGCUGAGCCCCAGAGCCCCAGAAACCUGCGGGAAGCUCCAAAGGGGGGCCUGCCAGAGGAUACACAACCACCCUACCUCCUGCACACGGGAUCCUCCAACCAGACAGUGUGGCCCAAGCAGCCUGGCUACUUUCACCUUAGCCAGCAGCCCUGGGCCACACUGGGGAUGGUCCCAAACAUGGCCUGUGCUGCUGUCACGGUGCUAAGGGGCCUGGCAAGCACGGGGUCUUUCUUGCUGGACGGAGGCACAGGUGCCAGAAUCUAUCUUUUGCCCUACAGUGUCCCGGCACAGCCUAGAUCUAUGGACCCCUUCACCGGGUGCUUUAUCCCCCACCCCCCAGAACUCCUGGGACCAUUGAGAUGCCCAGGAGAUGGGGGGGCCCUGUGCCUGUGUCCCGUUGCUGCUAUAGCAGCCACCACAUCUACCAGCUCUGCAGGGUAGCCACCGGGCACGGCCUUGCCAGGCUGACGUCGAGGAAAGCCAGCCGUGCUGUGGGUUUCCUUCCCUCUGGCUCUCCACUUCUGCCUCCCUCUUCCACUGUUUUUGGUUUGGGUUUUUGUUUUGUUCCGUUUUGUUUUUUUUUGAGACAGGGUCAGCUGUCUUGCCCAGGCUGGAGUUCAGGGGCUAUUCCCAGGUGUAACCCUAGCUCACUGCAACCUCCAACUGCUGGGCUUAAGUGAUCCUCCUGCCUCAGCCUGAGUAGCUGGGACUACAGGUGUGUGCUCCCACGUCUGGCAAGCCUCUUUCAGUAUAACUGUAUGGGUUUUUCUCCAUCUUUUUUUCGUCUUUACAAUUUUUGUUCUCAAGGACUUGGGCUGUUUGACUUGAGUCUUCCAGUCUGGAUUUUGCUGAUAAGAUGGAACACCUCGAGAGUGCAUCUUUGUUAACAUUUAGACAUGCGUCCCCUCCUCGCUUGCUCAGUGGAAUUACGAUUGCACUUGGAAAUGUAUCGUGUUGGGUGUGUUCCUUAAGCUGAACUUCCGUAGAUCUGGCAGGACAUUUAACACCAGAACACGAAGCCUGCUUCAGAAGUGACUGAAACGGCAUCUGCCUCACAGUGCAUAUUUAAAAAAUGAUUUUGUUGUGUGAAUAAUUAUGCUGCCAUCUACAGAUAAGUGAGAUCAGAAACAUUAGUUUCAUAUAUUGUAGUUUUUAGUUUCUGAAUACUUAUUGGAUUCUUUUUCUUUUUUUUUUGAGAUGGAGUUUCGCUCUGUUGCCAGGCUGGAGUGCACUGGGGCUUGGCUCACUGCUACCUCCGCCUCCCAGGUUCAGGCAAUUCUCCUGCCUCAGCCUCCUGAGUAGCUGGGACUACAGGCACCCACCACCACACCCAGCUAGUUUUUGUGUUUUUAGUAGAGACAGGGUUUCACCAUGUUGGCCAGGAUGGUCUCGAUCUCUUGACCUUGUGAUCCGCCCGUCUCAGCCUCCCAAAGUGCUGGGAUUACAGGCGUGAGCCACCAGGCCUGGCUCCUUUUCCACUUUCAUGGACCCUCGUGAUUGCAUUGGAUCUCCCCGGGUAAUCUGGGAUGUUCUUCCUGGCCUAAGGUCAGCUGAUUAGCAACCUUAGUUCAUCUGCAGUCUCCAUUCUCUUUUUGCUGAAUCACGUCAAGUAUUCACAAGUUCCAGGGGGCAGGAGGUGGACAUCUUUGGGGGACAUUAUUCCGCCCACCAGAAAACCCAGGAGCAGCCACAGCCCCAAGACGAGGCAGGGAAGGAGUGCUGCUGUCUGCCGGUGAAGAUGAACUGCUUCUGACCCUCCCGAGCGAGGAUAUUGAGAAGAAAGAAUUUGCCAAGAUGCUAGUCACACACCAAGUACAGAGGCUAUGUUGGUCGGCUGCAGCAAAAAGACCACUCGCGGCGUGGCAGCUCUCACUGGCCCUGCUGCCUCUUCAAGUUGACUGCAGUCCAUCACCCACGGUCAUUAUUAAUUUGUUUUUGCAAAGGCCAGGCAGGUGAAUCUAAUGGAGAUGGAAACCACCACACCUGCUUCCCUGGUCUCUGAUGUUGGUGUUAACCUCUGCAAUUCCUCAAGCAAAGCACUCCUUCUAUCAGGCUCACUGUCUUGCUGGAGGGAGGAAGUUCCACAGGCUCUCACUUGGUUCUUUCUGCCGUAACAACCCUUACUCCUCCGGCCAAGGAGCCAAUGUGAGCAUUCAGCUGGCAGCUAAGAAUGUGUAUCCCAAUAAACAGGGCAGACCUACAGACCCACUGGACCCACUAGAGAUGGACUUGGGCCACAGUGCCUUCCAUGACUUCAGUAAACAGAGGGGUGUGGUGAUCUUGUCAAAGUCCUGGCGUCAAUGUCAGUGUCCGGCUACACACCAUGUUCCCGUCCUCGAAAAGCCUCUCUGUACCCCUCUAUGUUGGUGACACAACCCUGGCAAAUGGCCACAGACUCCUUUGGGGACAGAGUAGGAGCGUAACUGGUGGGAGUGGUUGGCAUGCUUUGUAUUGGGAGAGCCGCACGCCCUAGGGCUUCCAGCCUCCUCUUCAGUUUGGCAGCUGUGAGUCUGAAUUUCACUCAAAUCUGGAAACUGGGUGAGAGACUGUGGCAGCUGCUGUCCGGCUGGCAGAGCCUGACGUGUCUCUGAUCAUACUCACUGGGUCAGCAACACCCUACUGACCUUGUCCAGAAUCCCACAUCCCAGUUGAUAUCAGGGCAAUCAGUUUCCUGGCUGUUUUCCCCAAUAUCAACCCGGGCUUACAGAAGACAGUCACCACAGAGCUCCUGCCAGGAGUUCACUCAUUCGUGCAUUUCUUCCUUUUUUUUUUCUUUUUGAGAUGGAGUCUCGCUCUGUCGCCCAGGCUGGAGUGCAGUGGAGCGAUCUCGGCUCAUUGCAACCUCCGCCUCCUGGGUUCAAGCGAUUCUCUUGCCUCAGCCUCCCAGGUAGCUGGGAUAGCAGGUGUGUGCCACCAUGCCCAGCUAAUUUUUGUAUUUUUAGUAGAGAUGGGGUUUCAUCAUGUUGCCCAGGCUGGUCUCAAAUUCCUGACCUCAGGUGAUCUGCCCUCAGCCUCCCAAAGUGCUGGGAUUACAGGCUUCAGCCACCACACCCAGCCUCAUUCAUACAUUUCUUAUUGUUGUUGUUUGAGACAGGGUCUUUCUCUGUCACCCAGGAUGGAGUGCAGUGUUGUGAUCAUGCCUCAGUGCAGCGAUCAUGGCUCAGUGCAGCCUCAAACUCUUGGGCUCAAGCAGUGCUCCAACCUCAGCCUCCUGAGUAGCUAGGACUAUAGGCACACAGCACCAUGCCCCGGCUAUUUUUUUAUUUUGUAGAGAUGGGGUCUCACUAUGUUGCCCAGGCUAGUAUUGAACUCCUGGCCUCAAGCAAUCCUCCCACCUCGGCCUCCCAAAGUGCUGGGAUUAAAGGCGUGAGCCACCGUACCUUGCCCUUGGUGGAAUCUUUAGGGUUUUCUAUUCAUACAUAUAAAAUCAUAUCAUUGGCAAACAGAGAUAAUUUUACUUCCUCCUUUCCAAUUUGGAUGCCUUAGAUUUCUUUUCCUUGCCUAACUGCUCUGUCUAGAACUCCCAGCACUAUGCUGAAUAGAGUGGCAAGAGCAGGCAUUUGCCUUGUUCCUAACCUUAGAGAAAAAUCCUUCAGCCUUUUACCAUUGAGGAUGAUGUUUGCUGUUAGUUUUUCAUAAAUGAUCUAUAUCAGGCUGAAUAAAUUUCUAUUUCUA